CUUCCUUUCCAACUUGGACGCUGCAGAAUGGCUCCCGCAAAGAAGGGUGGCGAGAAGAAAAAGGGCCGUUCUGCCAUCAACGAAGUGGUAACCCGAGAAUACACCAUCAACAUUCACAAGCGCAUCCAUGGAGUGGGCUUCAAGAAGCGUGCACCUCGGGCACUCAAAGAGAUUCGGAAAUUUGCCAUGAAGGAGAUGGGAACUCCAGAUGUGCGCAUUGACACCAGGCUCAACAAAGCUGUCUGGGCCAAAGGAAUAAGGAAUGUGCCAUACCGAAUCCGUGUGCGGCUGUCCAGAAAACGUAAUGAGGAUGAAGAUUCACCAAAUAAGCUAUAUACUUUGGUUACCUAUGUACCUGUUACCACUUUCAAAAAUCUACAGACAGUCAAUGUGGAUGAGAACUAAUCGCUGAUCGUCAGAUCAAAUAAAGUUAUAAAAUUGCCUUCAUGUUUUUGUUCUUUUUAGUUGCAACAUAAUGUACUUGUAUACCCUAUCCUAAUUAUGGGAUCAUUUGAAGAGCUUUUCCCAAAUUGAUGGCCUGUGCUGCCUUCUCCCCAUCCCCUGGGGUUUUAAAGUGAUUUCAAACUGCAACCUAGUUUUAGAACCACUGUUCUGGGUAGUUGGGAUACUGAAGGCAUAUUGUUAAUUAUUCUACUUGUAUGUUUUGCUAAUUCUAAGAUAAGCAUUUUUCCAGAAACCAGGAUGUAGAAUCCAGUUGCCAUUGACAUCUUAACAUUUUAGGAAACAACUUUAAAAUGAUAUACUAUCUAUCUAUCUAUCUGUAGCAUCUUAAAGGUAAUGAAAUUAAUGUGGCAGUAGGUCUUUUAAGCUUCUGCCUACAUCCAUAUUGAGUAUAGUUGUUGUCUUCUAAAAUAAUUAAUUGAUUUUUGGUGAGAUAACCAGAUUCAUAUUUUAAGCCUUUUGUAAUGGCCCCGUGGUACCUGGAGUCAAGGUUCAGAAGUAAAAAGUUCCUUAAGGUAUCAAUAACAAAAAUUUGUAUUAAUAGUUCAGUCCUAAAGCAGUGUUGCUGAGAUUAUGUUUCACCAGCAUUUACAAGCUGUAUGUUAAAUGCUGCCAUAAAGAGGUCUCUGAAGCCGUAGGGCACACCCAAGGCAGGGCUGAGAAGUACCUAGUAGUGUUGCACCACCCAAAAACCAUGGAUGGGCAGCAGCAACAUCUCCAGCUUACCCAUUCACUGCCACAGUCUACAGCUUAAGACACUUAACUACAAGGUAAAAGAAAAGGACCAAGUAAAUACAAAAAGUUUCUUAUUAAAAAACUUGGAAGCCAA